AUGGCGACUGAACCCUGCUUGUGGCACUCCAGGCUCAGUGGCUGGCAGCCGUGCAGGUCCAAGCCUGGGUCCCCUCUAGCACGAGUGGCUGCGUUUUGGUCUGUUCUGCCAGGCCUCCUGCAGGAGCUCAGGCCAGACCAGUGGCCUCCUACGAAUUUUAUCAAACGCGACUCAGACGAUGCCGUUCAGGCAAGGUUGAGAACCAAGCCCAGCACUGCCUGGUCCAGCCCCUGGGAAGGAAGGCAGGGCCGGGAGCCCCUCCUGCCGCCAGCAGCGACCCUGUCUCGGAAGGUUGUCUUUUCAGGGACGCUUGUACAGCAGACAGCCUUGGAAGAAAGAGAGAGAGUCUCACUCAGGAGCUCAGGACAGGUAUGCUUACUGCCUGUUAUAAAAGAUUCGGGUUCUCUAACAACAGGGUCAUCUCCUGCAAUGCACACCGCUGCUUGCAGGGGUACCUCACCCUCUUCACAUCCCCCCACAGGAGCUGGGGCUCAGGAGCCAUGGUGCACGGACAUGCUGGCCCUGACUCUGCACUACUGGGGGGUGAUAAAGACCUUUGUAUCUGACCCAGGAGUCUCGUGUCCUCUGCCUGCAUUCAUGAAACUGUGGGUGGCUACCUCGUUCAUUCGCAAGGACCUGUGAAAGGAAAAUAAAUCUUGGGACCGCAAAGUCACUAAGCCAAAGGGAAAAGUCACACUGGGAACUGUCAGGCGAGCCUGCUCCCAUUUUAUUCCCAAAUAAGACAGAUACAGAGAUUAAAAAAACAAAAAAGCCACACACCUCCCUCACAAUUUGUGCACAAGGAAAUUCCCCGUGGGGCUCAAGAUCUUUACCCUAGAGCAGUUGUGUGGGAUUUCACCCUGGCAAUGUCAGUGGACAGCUUACCUUCACAGGUGCAGAUGAAGGACAGAACUCAAAGCCAUCCCUCUGCUCCCCUGAGACAAACGCAUAUCUGACUGCUUCCUCGGCCCUGUUGUCUCACUGAGCCAGACUAAGGCACACGUGGCCCUUCCCCUACCCCCUCUCACAUGUGGAUUGUGUAUUCAGUGAAAGGCUGAUCAGAGACUCAUAGAAUGCAACCAUCUAUUGCUUAUCAACAUUAACUGGAAGCCGCUGCUUCGAGUUGUCUCAAG